GUGACUGGCCCACUGGUGCUCUAGGCCCAAGCACUUUCCACCAAAGCAAUCGUGGCGGAGGGGGUAGGCGGGAGGCGGGAGGCGGAGGGUACCCGUGGUGGAGUACCCCUUUCUUCCAACAAACGGAAAGAUGCCACGAAGAAGGGCUGUUGAUUUGUGGGGGAUUUUGAAGAGAGGAAGAGUAGGAGGAAGGGGUUGAGGGGCUGCCUCUGGCAUAUGCACACACUCACACAUUCUGUCACACCCGUCACACACACAUACCAUGUUCUCCAUCCCCCCAGGUCCAGCCCUCAGUGCUGUCCCAUCCAGCAGGGCUGCCCUGAAGCUCUGGCUGCAGCCCUCCCGUCCAGUGGGCAGGCGGCUUCAUCCCUCCUUUCUCUCCCAAAGCCCAACUGCUGUCACUGCAUGCUCUGCCAAGGAGGAGGGAACUGCAGUGACAGCAGGAGUAAGAGUGGGAGGCAGGACAGAGCUGGGACACAGGUAUGGAGAGGGGGUUCAGCGAGCCUAGAGAGGGCAGACGAUCAGGGUGCCGGCGGUGAGAAUCCAGGGAGAGGAGCGGAAACAGAAGAGGGGCAGAAGACCGGGGCACUUGUGGGUUGCAGAGCCCCUCAGCCAUGUUGGGAGCCAAGCCACACUGGCUACCAGGUCCCCUACACAGUCCCGGGCUGCCCUUGGUUCUGGUGCUUCUGGCCCUGGGGGCCGGGUGGGCCCAGGAGGGGUCAGAGCCCGUCCUGCUGGAGGGGGAGUGCCUGGUGGUCUGUGAGCCUGGCCGAGCUGCUGCAGGGGGGCCCGGGGGAGCAGCCCUGGGAGAGGCACCCCCUGGGCGAGUGGCAUUUGCUGCGGUCCGAAGCCACCACCAUGAGCCAGCAGGGGAAACCGGCAAUGGCACCAGUGGGGCCAUCUACUUCGACCAGGUCCUGGUGAACGAGGGCGGUGGCUUUGACCGGGCCUCUGGCUCCUUCGUAGCCCCUGUCCGGGGUGUCUACAGCUUCCGGUUCCAUGUGGUGAAGGUGUACAACCGCCAAACUGUCCAGGUGAGCCUGAUGCUGAACACGUGGCCUGUCAUCUCAGCCUUUGCCAAUGAUCCUGACGUGACCCGGGAGGCAGCCACCAGCUCUGUGCUACUGCCCUUGGACCCUGGGGACCGAGUGUCUCUGCGCCUGCGUCGGGGGAAUCUACUGGGUGGUUGGAAAUACUCAAGUUUCUCUGGCUUCCUCAUCUUCCCUCUCUGAGGACCCAAGUCUUUCAAGCACAAGAAUCCAGCCCCUGACAACUUUCUUCUGCCCUCUCUUGCCCCAGAAACAGCAGAGGCAGGAGAGAGACUCCCUCUGGCUCCUAUCCCACCUCUUUGCAUGGGACCCUGUGCCAAACACCCAAGUUUAAGAGAAGAGUAGAGCUGUGGCAUCUCCAGACCAGGCCUUUCCACCCACCCACCCCCAGUUACCCUCCCAGCCACCUGCUGCAUCUGUUCCUGCCUGCAGCCCUAGGAUCAGGGCAAGGUUUGGCAAGAAGGAAGAUCUGCACUACUUUGCGGCCUCUGCUCCUCCGGUUCCCCCACCCCAGCUUCCUGCUCAAUGCUGAUCAGGGACAGGUGGCGCAGGUGAGCCUGACAGGCCCCCACAGGAGCCCAGAUGGACAAGCCUCAGCGUACCCUGCAGGCUUCUUCCUGUGAGGAAAGCCAGCAUCACGGAUCUCAGCCAGCACCGUCAGAAGCUGAACCAGCACCGUAUGGGCUAGGGUGGGAGGCUCAGCCACAGGCAGAAGGGUGGGAAGGGCCUGGAGUCUGUGGCUGGUGAGGAAGGAAGGAGGGUGUAUUGUCUAGACUGAACAUGGUACACAUUCUGCAUGUAUAGCAGAGCAGCCAGCAGGUAGCAAUCCUGGCUGUCCUUCUAUGCUGGAUCCCAGAUGGACUCUGGCCCUUACCUCCCCACCUGAGAUUAGGGUGAGUGUGUUUGCUCUGGCUGAGAGCAGAGCUGAGAGCAGGUAUACAGAGCUGGAAGUGGACCAUGGAAAACAUCGAUAACCAUGCAUCCUCUUGCUUGGCCACCUCCUGAAACUGCUCCACCUUUGAAGUUUGAACUUUAGUCCCUCCACACUCUGACUGCUGCCUCCUUCCUCCCAGCUCUCUCACUGAGUUAUCUUCACUGUACCUGUUCCAGCAUAUCCCCACUAUCUCUCUUUCUCCUGAUCUGUGCUGUCUUAUUCUCCUCCUUAGGCUUCCUAUUACCUGGGAUUCCAUGAUUCAUUCCUUCAGACCCUCUCCUGCCAGUAUGCUAAACCCUCCCUCUCUCUUUCUUAUCCCGCUGUCCCAUUGGCCCAGCCUGGAUGAAUCUAUCAAUAAAACAACUAGAGAAUGGUGGUCAGUGAGACACUAUAGAAUUACUAAGGAGAAGAUGCCUCUGGAGUUUGGAUCGGGUGUUACAGGUACAAGUAGGUAUGUUGCAGAGGAAAAUAAAUAUCAAACUGUAUACUAAAA